ACAGAGCCACCAAGCAGUGCUGCAUACGGGGUCCACCUGUGUGCACCAGGAUGCCUGACACCAUGCUGCCCGCCUGCUUCCUCGGCCUACUGGCCUUCUCCUCCGCGUGCUACUUCCAGAACUGCCCGAGGGGCGGCAAGAGGGCCAUGUCCGACCUGGAGCUGAGACAGUGCCUCCCCUGCGGCCCCGGGGGCAAAGGCCGCUGCUUCGGGCCCAGCAUCUGCUGCGCGGACGAGCUGGGCUGCUUCGUGGGCACGGCUGAGGCGCUGCGCUGCCAGGAGGAGAACUACCUGCCGUCGCCCUGCCAGUCCGGCCAGAAGGCGUGCGGGAGCGGGGGCCGCUGCGCCGCCUUCGGCGUUUGCUGCAACGACGAGAGCUGCGUGACCGAGCCCGAGUGCCGCGAGGGCUUUCACCGCCGCGCCCGCGCCAGCGACCGGAGCAACGCCACGCAGCUGGACGGGCCGGCCGGGGCCUUGCUGCUGCGGCUGGUGCAGCUGGCCGGGGCGCCCGAGCCCUUCGAGCCCGCCCAGCCCGACGCCUACUGAGCCCCGCGCUCGCCCCACCGGCGCGCUCUUCGCGCCCGCCCCUGCAGCACGGACAAUAAACCUCCGCCAAUGCA